AGAGCCUGCCUGGAGCGCGUACUCAGCGGCUCUCGGGUCCCAGCGUCCCAGCCGCGGCCCGCGCUCCUCCGCCCCGCUCCUCCUCCUCCUCUUCCUCCUCCUCCUCCUCUCUAGGCACCCCCGUCCCCUCCUUCCAGCGGCUGCAGCCCCCAGCCCCAACUCUCCGCGCUUACUCCUGGGACGCGCGUCCUCGCCCCAUCCUUUGCUUCCUUCCUUCCUUCCUUCUUCCUUCCUCCCCUGGCUCCCGCCCUCCCUCUCCAGGUCGCCCUCCCGGGGCCCGAUUGUCUCGGUGCCCCGCUCCCGGCCCGCGCCCUGCCCCGUCUCUCCCUUGCACUUCCUGAGUCGCCCGCCGCCGCCGUCGCAGACUCGCCGCGGGAGCCCCAGCCCAACCCGAGCCCGACAGCCACUGCCCCGGCUCCAGCUCCAGCCCCACAGCCCGCGGCGCCCGCCCGAGGGAGCCCCGGCGCCCGGGGAAGGCUCCAGUGGGCUAGCGCGCCCUCGCCCAGCCCCGCGCCCCAGCCCUGCCCGGCCCGGCGAGGAAGGACCGGGAAGAUGAACAACGGCGGCAAAGCCGAGAAGGAGAACACCCCGAGCGAGGCCAACCUUCAGGAGGAGGAGGUCCGGACCCUAUUUGUCAGUGGCCUUCCUCUGGAUAUCAAACCUCGGGAGCUCUAUCUGCUUUUCAGACCAUUUAAGGGCUAUGAGGGUUCUCUUAUAAAGCUCACAUCUAAACAGCCUGUAGGUUUUGUCAGUUUUGACAGUCGCUCAGAAGCAGAGGCUGCAAAGAAUGCUUUGAAUGGCAUCCGCUUCGAUCCUGAAAUUCCGCAAACACUACGACUAGAGUUUGCUAAGGCAAACACGAAGAUGGCCAAGAACAAACUCGUAGGGACUCCAAACCCCAGUACUCCUCUGCCCAACACUGUACCUCAGUUCAUUGCCAGAGAGCCAUAUGAGCUCACAGUGCCUGCACUUUACCCCAGUAGCCCUGAAGUGUGGGCCCCGUACCCUCUGUACCCAGCGGAGUUAGCGCCUGCUCUACCUCCUCCUGCUUUCACCUAUCCCGCUUCACUGCAUGCCCAGGUGUCCAGCCCCCCACCUGCCAUGGGGGCUCUGUGUCCCCGCCCCGUCCUUUCCCACCUGUCUCAGGAAGGCAGCUCCAACUCUGCUCUUUGCUUAGUGAGCAAGUGGAUUCAGAUGCACCAGGCCAUGAGCCGUGGAUGCGCUGGCUCCCUCCCUCCGAGGCUACUUCUCAGGGCUGGAAGUCCCGUCAGUUCUGCUGAAUACUAUACCCUUCAGCAAUGGCUACUAGAAGGACGAACAAUUGCCCUCCUUUGGAAGUACGGCUAAUAGAAGCCCUAGAUCCGAAUAAGAUCCGAAUAAGAAUAUGUAAUGGACCAGGCGCAGUGCCUCACGCCUGUCAUCCCAGCACUUUGGGAGGCUGAGGCAGGCGGAUCACUUGAUGCCAGAAGUUUGAGACCAGCCCAGCCAACAUGGUGAAACCCCGUCUCUACUAAAAAUACAAAAAUUACCCAAGCAUGGUGGUGGGCGCCUGUAAUCCCAGCUACUAGGGAGGCUGAGGCAGGAGAAUCGCUUGAACCCGGGAGGCAGAGGUUGCAGUGAGCCAAGAUCAUGCCACUGUACUCUGGCCUGGGCGACAGAGCAAGACUGUCGAAAAAAAAAAAAAAAAAGAGUAUGUAAUGUCUCCCGUGGAUGAAUCAUUUGUUCUGAGCUAAGCUUGGGCCAUGGGCCAGACUCCUUCCUCGGAGCCUGUGGGGAGCAGGUGAGGAAGGAGUAUGGAUAAUGGUGCCCGUUACUCCUGCACGCGGGGGAGUCUAGUCUCCCAGCCCAUCUAAAGUUAGACUAGCUCAGUGCGGAUCUAUUAUUUCAGCUCCUUCUAGUCUCUUGGAUCAAGUCCUUUCCAAGAUGGCCCAUAAUCCAAGCUGUGUAAUCUUAGGCAAAUGUAAAUUAGAAUUGGAAACAGUGGUGCUGAUGAGCUAAUAUAAACAUUUUUAAACCAGAACAAGUCAAAAAGGCCAAAUGAAAGGCGCAUACCAUUCAUUGGCAGAGGCCCACAUGGCUCUCUCCGUUCGGCGGGGAGGGCUUUCUUCCCCAUCUUGCUUUCCCAGCACGGAAAGAACAGAAGACGAGCAGGAGUGAUGCCGUCCUUCCAAAUCCUCAAAGGCCAGCACUCCCAGAGGUCCUUCAAGGAUUUUUCAUUUAUCUACUUGGACUUCUUAGUGCUAAAGAGAAAUCAGUGACUAGACUAGAUAUGUAAAUAAGAACUUUAUUCUCUAGACAAACAUUUGUUGUGUCUGCUGUGUCCAAGAUACAAAAAUGAAAAAACAGGCCUGUGCCCCUCAGGAGCUUAAGUUCUAAUGGCAGAGAACUGUGGACACAUGUACAGGAGAGGGAGUUACUGCUCAUGAUCCUGCAAGACCAGCUUGCUGUGAGGAGAGCCAAGCUGAGGGCAUGUACAGGCCAUGUGCAUGCUGUUCCUGUGGCAUAAGCAAGGCCAUCAGGAGAGGGGGGGUCAGAAGGGGACAGGGUGUUACUGGUGUUUUAAUUUGCUCCGCCUCUUGCUGAUGGAUGGUGUUGAGUUUAGUGAUGCAGACACAGCCUGUGGCCAGAGUUUUGCUGAUGGUUCAGCCAUGUGCUAGAGAGCCCAGAAUACAGAAUCACGAUUGAAAAUUGUCAGUUUCCCAGAUACACUGAGAACAGGCGAGCAUGAGCAACGCUGCUGUCACUCCUUACAUGCAGUGAGAGUGAGGCAGCUUUCUUUGAUGGAUAUUCAAAGAGUUGAACUGUUCUUGAAAGGGAAGAACCAGCGUUUGGGAGCCAAGUGGGGUGUAGGGGGACGUCUUCUUUCAGGACUCUUGAAAUUUUCCUGGCCAUGGACCGGGACCAGAGCCCAGAAAUUAUAAGCACAUGUAGUUACAGCCUCCCCAGAUUGGAGAAGGAAAUGCAAGAGAGAACGUGACGGAAUUUGGAGCUAUUUUUCCCUUCUCUUCUGUUUUGGGUGGAAUGGCCUUGCCUGUCUUUGGCUGUGAGCUUGAGUCAUCCUCAGUAGAGUCCCAGGUGCUGGUGCCCAGGUGGAGCUUAGAGCUUAACAAGGAGGAAAGGCACUGGGGCUCCAGAGGCCCAGACAGCUGCGGUGGCUCCUGCUGUCACGCUGGCCUCCCCUUAGAAGAAAGCCACCUGUCCAUGUCAUGCUAUCACACUGCGGUGCACCCACCAACCAGUAUGAGGCUGUGAGGUCUGCACAUCACACCUAAGGCUACUAACGCCGUAACUGUCCGUCAUACCUAAGGCUAAUACGGUGAGCAGCUGCAGCGUCCUGGGGAGGAGAUGGGUAAUAGGUAAUCAAAUAGACAUAAUAGUUUGGGUGGUGAUAGUAUUCAGGGAAUAAAUAAUAAGGCCAGGUAAGCAGCUCAGUGUUGUGGUACGGCCAGCACUUCUGGUGCCUUCUGCUUCAAGUUAGCAAAGCAGGCAGGGUCCGCCUGAGAAGGUAACAUCUCAGCAAAGACCUAGAACUUCACCAGCUUUAUACGGGGUUUCUUUUUCAGAACACAUUCCACUUUAGUGAGGCUUGGAAAAUAUUUAACUCCUGUAAUCUUAAAGUAAAUGGACUGGAAGUGCAGCAGGCUUGGCUCCCACGCAGCACUAAGGAAUCACUGGGAGAGUGUGCAGGGCCCUCCUCAGAGACCUUUCUCUGUUU